GCUUCACAGGCGCAGCGACAGCGACAGCGACAGCUCGAACCUGAGUCCCAGGAUUCCGGGGACUGGAGGGCAGCGCCGGCAGCCAAGAGAUGGUGUUUCACUAUGUUGCCCAGGCUGGUAAGUGAUCUGUUUAUAUUUGUCAAGUUUGUGAAUGAAUGAAUGAAUGAAUGAAUGAAUGAAUAAACCAAUAACCUUGGAUACUUUUCCUCUUUGAGCCUCAGUUUUCUCCUCUAUAAAAACAAUAUUUAAAAAAGUCUAACACCUACUCUGCCUACCUCACCAGGUUAGUGUGUAUGUGUGUGUGUGAGAGAGAGAGAAAGAGAAAGAACAAAAUGUAUGAAUGUUCUUUGUCUCCUGCGCACUGGAAUUUAAAAGUCACUUUGUCUCAGGCUCUGUGCUUUAACCUUGGUGUUGGUGUUCCAUAUCAGGAGGAAGGACUAUUUUCCAGUGUCUGGUAAACACUUAGUUCUCCAUCCUGUAUUCUAAGUAUCUUAAGGACAGGAGAACAUUUUAUUUAUUUAUUUAUUUAUUUAUUUAUUUAUUUAUUUAUUUAUUUAUUCAUGUAUGUCAGCAUCUUGCCCUGUCAUCCAUGCUGGAGUGCAGUGGCGUGAUCUUGGCUCACUGCAGCCUCAACCUUCCCUGCUCAAGCCAUCCUCCCACCUCAGCCUCCUGAGUAGCUGGGACUGCAGGCCUUUGCCGCCACACCCAACUAAUUUUUAUAUUUCUUUGGGUAAAGACAGGGUUUCAUCAUGUUGCCCAGUCUUGUCUCAAACUCUUAGGCUCAGGUGAUCUUCCCACCUCUGCCUCCUGAAGUGUUGGGAUUACAGGCAUGAGCCACUGCACCCAGCCUAUUUUAAAUGCUUUUAACCGAUUGGUUUAAAUUUGAGAACAAAGAAUUUUAAGGUUCUCAGCCUCAGCUUAUAGCCACUGCCCUGUUGGUCCCUUACUUGGCCCCAGAACCCUGGAAACCUUCCCAGGACAGAGCUUGCCUUACUUCCAACCACAGAUCUUCAUCAGGUGCAGGAGGAAUUCGACCUUCAGAUCUUUGCCCAUGCACUUGGCUCUGCCUGAAGCAUUCUCUUUGCUUUUUACCCGUCCAAUUCCAGCACAUCCUUCAGAUCCCAGGUUAGACUCCCUUCUUCCAGGAUACGUUCCCAGCUCCUCUCUGCCCUGUCAGGUAAGCUUCCUCCUCCAUGCCCUCCCUCUUUGUGUCCUCUAUCUGAGUGCUCACCCUGCUGAACUGUGGUUUCCCAUCAGUCGUCUGCCUCCCUUUUAAACUGUGGCCCCCUGAGGACUAUGAUUGUGUCUUCCUUGUUCAUUGAUGUAACCUUGGUACAUAUCACAGUGCCAGGUACCAAGAGGAUAUUCUACAAAUAGGCAUUGAUUAAGUGACUGGCAACAGUGUGUUGAGGAGAUGGGAGAGAGGGUGACAAAUCACAAAGGUCCCCAUAGGAGGGUAUUGUAUUUCCUGAAGUAUGAGAAACAACACUUCCACCAAAAUGGCUUGCAUAGCUAAGGAUGCAAAGCUUUGGUGCAUAACUUGCAUAAACUAAGGAUGCAAACACACCCCCAGACAUUCCUGGACACACCCUACUGUAGGCAGUCAUUCAUUUAACACACUUGCCCUUGCUCUGAAAUUUCUCCUCUUAUCGUCUCCUUCCACUCAUCUUUCUCAUUUCCUGUAUAAGGGAAUUGCAAGACUAAAAGAAUCUAACUGGCAGCAAAAAGAUAAUGCCAGAGAAAGAGAUUAUAUUGCCACACCUUUGCUUAAGGUUUUUUCCCCUCUUUCUCUGCCUGUUAGAUUUCUGCACCAUUCCAUUGUAAGGAAAUUCUACUUAUCUUUAUUAUGGACAAUUCCUGAAGACACCUGAACUUUGAAAAAUAGCUUAGUAUGUGGUUCUGCCCACUCUUUGGAGUCCUGCCAAAGGUGUCUUUCAGCAAAUAGCCCCCAACUCCGUGCCUCAGUUUCCCUCUUUUCUCUCACAGAGAUGAGAAACAGAAGUUGUCCUUGAAACUUUUUUUUGAAAAUAAAAGCGCCCCCACCCCCCGACUUCUUUGUUUUAUUUUUAACAAAAUAAAACCUGUCUCUCACUCUGUCACCCAGGCUGGAGUGCAGUGGCAUGAUCAUAGCUCACUGUAGCCUUGAACUCAUGGCCUCAAGCGAUCCUCCCACCUCAGCUUGCCAAGUAGCUAGGACUACAAGUGUGCAUCACUAUGCCCAACUAAUUUUUUUUUUUAAUUGAGAUAGGGUCUCACUUUGUUGCCCAGCCUGGGGUCUCAAACUCCUGGCUCAAAUGAUCCUCCCGCCUCAGCCUCUUAAAGUUCUGGGAUUACAAGCGUGAGCCACCCGCACCCAGCCCUGACUAAUUUUUGAAUUUUUUUGUAGAGGUGAGGUCUCACUAUGUUGCCCAGGCUGGUCUUGACUCCUGGUUUCAAGCAAUCCUCUUGCCUUGGGCUCCCAAACUGCUGAGAUUACAGGUGUGAGCCACCGCACCAGUAGAAGAGCUCCUUAAAUAUGCAGUUACUUGCUGGUCAUGACCAUGGAAUGUGAAGGAAAGGAAGGUGUCACUUAAUUCUUCUAUGGGCAGGUGAAUUUUAAGUUCUUAAGGUUGACUCAAAUGUGGUCAGAGACUCAAGUGAAAACUUGCCCUACCCAAAGAAAGAGUCCUGAACUGGCCUUGAAGAGGAGGAGGAUUUCUGAAGCAGUUUAGAGUGUUGUUGGUAAGGACCCAACUGGCAGCAGAUACAGCAUGAUAAAAUCACAGAAGCCUGGCAGGGUGCGGUGGCUCAUGCCUAUAAUCCCAGCACUUUGGGAGGCCAAGGCGGGUGGAUCAUGAGGUCAGGAGAUCGAAACGAUCCUGGCCAAUAUGGUGAAACCCUGUAUCUACUAAAAUACAAAAAAUUAGCCGGGCGUGGUGGUAGGCGCCUGUAGUCCCAGCUACUUGGGAGGCUGAGGCAGGAGAAUGGCUUGAACCUGGGAGGCGGAGGUUGCAGUGAGCUGAGAUCACGCCACUGCACUCCAGCCUGGCAACAGAGUGAGACUUCGUCUCAAAACAACAACAGCAACAACAAAAUCACAAUCACAGAAGCCGGAAAGUGUUUUCUGAGCCCCAGGAACAUCAGGCGGUCUUACCCUGUUAGGAUGCUGGUCAAGUCUUUCGUGGUAUGCCUUCAUCUGACCUCCUGGCUUCGUCUGUCCACACCCUCUACCAUACUGCAGGCAUACAGGACCCACUUCCUAGGUUAGGGUUGCAAACUGGGGGUGCUCGGGUAAACUUGGACUGCUAGACAGGCUUUGUUUGGCUCAUAACAUCGUCUUUUGCAAUACUUUUUACUUAAGUCAAUUCCCAAAUUGGGAGACUUCACGUAAAAUCCAAAUCUUCACUUAUUUUGGAAAAAUAAAAGAUCUGGCAACAGAGGGCCACAUUCGUCCAUAAUAGCAAUCAGCUAGAGCCAGAAGUGAGUAGCUGCUGCCCCUUUCACAGAGGACUUGCUGUCUCCAGUCCCCACCACUCUGGUCAGCUGCCUUUGAUCAUCUUUUUUUUUUUUUUUUUUUUUAUUUUUUUUAGAGAUGAGGUCUUGCUAUGUUGCCUAGGCUGGUCUUUUACCACUGGCCUCAAGCAAUGUCCACCUAGAGCACUGGGAUUACCCCCAGACCCAGCCUGCCUUUGAUCAUCUUACCCCCCAGGACAUUUAUGUUGCCUGCUGUGCCUAAAGGCACUUGAGUUUCCUGACAUCUGCCUUGGGGAGGACCUUCUAUCCCCUGGGCUCCUGGUACAUCACACACCCUUCCUCCCUGCCCCCAUUGAUGCUGAUUUAUCCAGUAUUCUGGGGCUGGGGGCUGGGUUCUUUCUGCUUUCAAGGGGAUAAGUUCCCAUUCCAUAAAGACACACAAGGCCACAGGCUAAGGAACAGGCAGGGACCUGUUCUUUGCUUCCCAGAUAACACACACCCGCUUUAGCAAUAACCUUCUGGGAAUCAUGCCCGUGACUUUUCUUUUUUCUAUUCCAUUAGUGAUUUUCAAAGAGGAAGUUUCAGUCAGAUAAAAGGAGCAGAUGGCACUGUACGAGGCCUCCUGCCGGGUAAAUAUUUUGGAGGAGCCAGGGCUUUUCUGUGAGUUGCUCCUCUUGCCUGGUAAGCUUUGAUUUCCCAGGUUAUUGAGGUGUGUUCUCCUAAGGAAGGAAUCAGGCCUUACUUAACCUUGAUAAUUAAAAUCACUGUUCUCAUUGCCCUUCCUUCAUAAACAAGGAAAUUGGAACAGAGCUAAGAGAAGAUUUUUCAUGCAGUUUAGGAAAGAAUGAGCAAUGGAAAAAGGAAAUUGAGAGCUUUGGGGAGUUUAUAGCAGAGAGCAUUUGAGUUUGAAAUAGGAGCUGAGAAUCCAUAUGUUUGAGAGGAAAGAAAAGAAAAGAACAGCCACAUGCCCAGAGCUUCAAGGGGACGUGCGGAAAUUGUUAUAGGAAAGGGGGCAGGGAGGCCCACGUGGGUCUCCCUUUAUCAGACCCAGAUGUUCAGGCAACGGUUCUCAAGAUGCCCAUGAAAAGGUCUAGAGUCUGCUGAGCUAGACUCACUGUUUUCUUAACUACCAAGAGGCACAUGAAAUCAGUGGCCUGGAGCUUUCCACCGUGUGCUCAAUGGUUCCCUGAGGCCCUCCUGGGGUCUGUGCCGCACCAAUUAUACACAGACUGGGCUGCCUUAGGGCAGGACUUGAAAGUGAAUAGGACUGACUGGCUCACUGGGUAACUGUCCCUGCCUGUCAGCCCCUGCCAAACAGAGGCUGCCAAACCUCCCUCUGUUGCCUCCCGCCCCAGACUAACCUUGGAAGGCAGGAGACAUUGGAAGGUCCAGGUUCAGCUCUCAAUUCCACCUGGCAUAAAUGACUUAGCUUCUCUGAGCCUCAGUGUUGGUGUCUUUAAAAUGAGGAAAAAAAUCAUUUGUGAGGUGCAUAUAAGAUAUGUGUGAAAGGGCUCUACAAAGAAGAAAGCACAAAAUGUUUUUUAUUAUUCAUUAUCCUUUUAAAAAUUACUAACAAAAAUUUCAAAUAAAUGCUCAGGUAGGCGGAAUGAACCCUCAUAACCCAGCUUCAAGAAUUAUCAACUCAUGGCCAAUUUUAUUGUAUCUAUAUCUCCACCCACUUUCUCCAUCCCUGUGUUAUUUUGAAGCAAAUCCCAAAUAUUCUAUUAUAGUAUCUUACUAUCAAAUGUAUACAGCUGACUUGCUCCCUCAACCAAUGGAAACUUACCCAAUCUUCAGGUGUCCCUUUCUGCACCCCUUUUCCCUUCCAGGGGGCCACACCUCCUAUCCCCACCAUGCACCUGGUGCCCUAAACCUUCUCAAAUCCAUUAUUACUACGAAACUGUCAUCACUGAUAGUAGCUCAGGUUGUAAGCCCUGGGAAGCCUGAGAUGUAUUUGCAUUUUAUCAGGCCCCAUUGUCUUUAGAGAGAAGAGUGACUUCUAACAAGUAAACUAUGAAGUAUCACUCUCUAGAAGUAGCAGGAGGUGGUGAGCCAUUAAGGGCCCUCCAAACCCUUGACACCAAGCAUAAGCUCUAUAGGAAUUGGCUGAGUUCCUCCUCCUGUUGGUGCUUUUCUUCCAGGGAGAGGGCACACGGAGCAGAGAACACCGGUGAAUUAUGUCCUCUCAGCCUCUGACUGCAGGGGAAUCAGGGCUCUCCUCUCCUGGCAGAUGCUCUACUGCUGACUUGAAGUCUGUGACUAAGCUGUGAAUAUGAGACUCGGGUCUAUUCCCAAGUCCUCAUGCAGUGGAUAGGAUGCAAGCUCCAAAAGCCAGGAGACUUGAUUCAAAUCCUGCCUCCACUAUUUAUAUCACAUAGCUUCUCUGUGCCUCACUUUCUCUUCCUUAUCUGUAAAGCAGGGGUUACAAUACUUACUUCACAGUUGUUGAAAGGAUCGUUAUGAGAUAAUGUCAUAUUCCUUAGGAUUCUUUUGGUAGCAGGUGAUAGAAAAUCCAAUUCAAGACUGGACACAGUGGCUCAUGCCUGUAAUCCCAGCACUUUGGAAGGCCAAAGCAGGAGGAUCACUUGAGGUCAGGAGUUCGAGACCAGCCUGGCCAACAUGAUGAAACCUUGUCUCUACUAAAAAUACAAAAAUUAACCAGGCAUGGUCGUGGGCGCCCAUAAUCCCAGCUACUCGGGAAGCUGAGGUAGGAGAAUCACUUGAAUCCAGGAGGCUGAGUUUGCAGUGAGCCGAGAUCAUGCCAUUGCACUCCAGCCUGGGCAACAGAGCAAGAGUCUGUCUCAAAAAAAAAAAAAAAUAGAAAUCCAAUCCAAGAUACUUUUGAGCAAAACAGGAGUGCAGGGGCUCAUCUUAAGAUGAAAAUUCCAAGGAUGGACAUGAUGGAUUUGGAGUUCAAAUGUUAGAGCGGGACUCUCCUUACGUCUUGGCUCCAUAUUCUGUCUUUUAACUUUAGUCUUGGGUUAAUGUAACAAGCUGACAGCAUCAGUUCUAGCCCCUAUAUCCUUUCAGGUCUGGGGUCAGAGAGAUUCUGACAAAAGUCUCAUUGACCCUGAUUGGGUCCCAUGAGCAUCCCUGAAACAAUCACUGUAAUCAAGGAAAAUGACAUGCACUUUGUUUUUUUUUUUUUUUUGAGAUGGAGUCUCGUUCUGUCGCCCAGGCUGGAGUGCAGUGGCGCGAUCUCAGCUCACUGCCAGCUCCGCCUCCCAGGUUCAUGCCAUUCUCCUGCCUUAGCCUCCCGAGUAGCUGGGACUACAGAUGCCUGCCACCACGCCUGGCUAAUUUUUUUGUGUUUUUAGUAGAGACGGGGUUUCACUGUGUUAGCCAGGAUGGUCUCGAUCUCCUGACCUCCUGAUCCACCCUCCUCGGCCUCCCAAAGUGCUGGGAUUACAGGCUUGAGCCACCGCGCCCGGCCAACAUGCACUUAUUUACUUGAGCUGAUGUCACUGCAUCUAUAGGGACUGAGAGAGCAGGAGGAGUGGUUCAUUACAGGGCAUUGCAGGGGUGUUGGGCAUGGUUACCCAAAUGAAGGUGAGGCCAGGCAUAGUGGCUUAUUCCUGUAAUCCUAACACUUUGGGAGGCCAAGGCAGGAGGAUCGCUUGAGGCCAGGAGUUAGAGACCAGCCUGGGCAACAUAGUGAGACCCUGUCUUUACAAUAAAAAUUAGCUCAGCCGGGCGUGGUGGCUCACACCUGUAAUCCCAGCACUUUGAGAGGCUGAGGCAGGCGGAUCAUGAGGUCAGGAGUUCGAUACCAGCCUGGCCAAUAUGGUGAAACCCCAUCUCUACUAAAAAUACAAAAAUUAGCUGAGCAUGGUGAUGCGUGCCUGUAGUCCCAGCUACUCAGGAGUCUGUGGCAGAAGAAUCGCUUGAACCUGGGAGGCGGAGGUUGCAGUGAGCCGAGAUCGUGCCACUGCACUCCAACCUGGGUGACAGAGUGAGACUCUGUCUCAAAAAAAAAAAAAUAAUAAUAAUAAUUAGCCAGCCAUGGUGGCGUGCACCUGUAGUCCCAGUUACUUGAGAGGCUGAGGCAGGUGGAUCACUUGAGCCCGGGAGGUCGAGACUGCAGUGAGCUAUGAUGGUGCCACUGCACUCCAGCCUGGGUGACAGAGUGAGAUACUGUCUCAAAAAAACAAAACAAAACAAAAGAAAAUGAAGUUGAAUAGAUACUAAUGGCAAAACUGAAGGUGCUUGCUAUAAAUGCUUUGUAAGUCCUCAGGCACAUUAUUGAAGAUCAUAAAACAAUAAUUCCCUUCUCCUAUCUCAUGGAGCAUUUUUUAUUCCUUUUCAAAUAAGUUUCACAUAUUUAAUAUCUUUGAGCUUCAUAACAGUCCUAUGAGACAAACAGGAGUACAGGUAUUGUCUUCCCAUUUUUACAGAUGAGGAAAUCAAAGCACAGAGCAGGUGAGGACUUUGCCCAUGGUCAACAUGGCAAGGUAGUGUGGACUGUGCUUAGAGUCACACAGAGACACAACUGGCUCUGAAUUCCCUGGCAGAUCCACUGGGACUGGAAACUAGGACAUUUAGGGUAUGGGUUAAUCAAGGCCUGCCCUGGGAUUUGGAUCACCCACCCAGGUUCAUUCCUGAGUAAACAGUUUAGACUGAUGGCAGUUGAGUAUGUCAAGGACCCAUUGUUGAUGCCCUGGCAGGUGGCAAGGGAAAGAACUGGAAGGAAAGACACUGGCACACGAGGAACACCCUCACAUGACUGAUCCCCUUUACACCAGGCAGCUGGGUACAAGACUUGGUCUUCCUCGUCCCAGAAAAAAAUGCCAAUCAAAAAUAAAACAAAAAGAAGGGGAGGCCACGCUGGUUGCAGGGCUGGUUCCUGGACUUCUUUCAAGGGAACUUGAUCCUGGAGCCAAGAGCAUCCUUUGCCAGGAUGUGGAGGGAGAGAAGAAUCCCCCAGUCAAAUGAGGAUGGUUUGGCCAGAGUCUCAGCAUCCUCUUAAGUGUUGCUGACAUCUCCAAAGAGUCUUCCAAAAACCGGAGUCCCUCCUCUGCCUCCAGGUUCUGAACACAUUGAGAAAGAAGACAAAGGAAUGGCAGGGAGCCAACAUACCACCUUAAUUACCACUAAAGCUAGCAUGGAGGUUGCAGCUGAGUGUGAGAACAAAAUGAGCUUCCUGACCGAGCCUGGGAGAAGGAUGGGGCUGAGCUGAUCAUUCCAGAGAGUCUUCCCAAGUCACCCAUUCAGAUCAGUCAUUCCAUUAUUGUGGACAGUGAGAGUGAAGAUAAAGAGGGGUGUUUAGGAAAAAUCUCUCCUUGUGAAAACCAAAAGCAGGAAAACAUGUGAGUGUGGCAAGGUAUUAAUCUCUCUGCACAUCAGUCGAGAUCUCUUCUUCAGUAUAAUGGGGAUAGUGACAGUGAGGGUUCUGUGGGAUCACGUGUAUGACGGUCCUGGCAUACAGUAAUCGCUCAGUAAAGGCUGUUUUUGUGUGCAGUCCAGGUUCAUGGCAGGUGGCCUUUCUUUCCUCCCCGGCAUGAAGCCCAGGGCCCCAGAGUCCUGCCGGGCUUGUGUAUCGCUCUUUCUCUCCAGCUGUAAAAAUUCAUGAGAAUGUGGGUGUGCGGUGGCUUUCCAGUUUCUUGGCUUCUCCCCAGGCUAUGUUCUCCCACUUGGGGGCAGGGGGGUGGCAGACAUCCUUUUCACAGUGGUGAGUGCCACCCCACCCCAACCCCCAUGCCCUGUCCCAGCAGAGUCUGGCUCAAAGUUCAAAGCCAGGGUGGCUUUGUUGAGUAAUUUGGUGACAUUGCCUGCCUGCCUGCCCACCAUGCUCUCACACGCCCAUUUGCUAGGCAUCUGCUGCCCUGUGUUUUGUGGUGUGGAGGAUGGGAACAGCUCACCCCCCCCCGACUGACCGCGGUGAGGCUCAGCUUCCUUCCUCUCCCCCGCCCUUGGGCUCUCAGUCCCACACACAGCCCCACUCAGUGAGGUUUCGGAUCUGCUCCCAGGCUGGUUGGCGCUGACUCCAUCUGGAUCCACACCAACCCCUUCCUCCUGGGGGUUCAGAGUGUUCUUGGAAGGAAGCCUGGGAAGGGAAAGGCCUUCUCCAGCAUUCCCCAUCCAGUGGUUGGCUGACAGCAUAGAACUGAGCUGCCAAGAACGCUGGAGUCAGACAGAACUGAGUUCAAAUCCCCGGGUGACCUUGGGCAAGCUGCUCUCUCUGCUUCAGUUUCCUCAUCUGUAAAAAAUGUGACAGUAACAGGAUCUGCCUCCUGGGAUGAUUGUGAGGAUUCAGGGAGAUACUAACUGUGAUGUCCUCACCCCUACAUCUGGCAGGUGGGAAGUGCUUAAGAAAUGGUGGCCCUGGAGCCAGGGAUCCCCUGCCUUCCCAUGGGUGUACUCACAGGGAGGAGGCGAACGCCGUCUCCUUUUGCUCAUCCCACCUCCCAAAUUAGACCCCUGCCGUAGUUACUCUGACAUGACCAAACUGGUUUGGUUUCCUGCAAACUCCUUUUGGACAAGGACUCUGUCUCAUUUGUCUUAUAACUCCCAUGCCUAGUGUGGUCCUGGCACUUACACAGCACUAAAUGUUUGGAAUAAAUAAGUGGAGGAUAAAGGAGCAAACGAGUGCCUGGUGGGCAGCAUCUGUUCAAGGACUGUUUUCUGAACUCCAGGCAGUUAUUUCUGUCCCUUCCAUUUUCCCUCUCUCCUUCCUCCCUCCCUCCCUUCCUUCUCUCCUUCCUUCCUUUUGACCUUCCUCUUCAGACCUCCUUUCCUUCUUGCUAAAUGGAAAGAGCUUCCUCCUUUCCUUUUCUUGUAAUAUCCAAGCUGCAAGAGCAUCCCUUGAGAGCCCUUCACCCAGCCGAGAGCAGCGAUUCCUCUUUCAAAUUGAGUCUGUCCCCUGACUCAUUCAUUAAAAUGCAUAGGGCAUGUGACCAAACUGCAUAAUGAGUCUCUCAUGAGGAAGGCUUGGAGGCAGGGAGAUGCUGCCAACUGCAAAGGCAAAUACUUCCCCCCCAGCUGUGGAUCAGGCUCAUUGGCUGUCAUACCCUGGGAAGGCUGGGGGCUGCAGUUCAUCUCCAGUAAAUCAGCCAAGCCCUGGAGAGCUGCAGCCUGGCGCAGGCUGUACGGUCUUGGAAGCUGUGUUGCUUUGGAGAAUCCAACCCAUGACUUUUCUCAACCUUCUUCCACCCAUUUCUAGUUUUUCAUUUAUUUAAAUAUACUUUUAACUCCAUAGGUGAUAUGCAAAUACAUGCUUAUCAUAAAAUAUGCAAACAUAAAAGAAAACCCCCUUUGAUAAUGUCUCUGUACUGCUACCUCUCUCGGAGACAAACAACUGUUGUCACUCAGCUCUUUACCUUCCAGGGCCCUUGGGCUGCUGGGUGACAGAUGUCCCAUGAAGGUGAUUUGGGAGCCCAAACACCCUUUUGCCCUCCUGAAGUCCUAGGCCAGUUCUCAGUAAAAACAGUCAACAUUCAUCUUAAGUGCCUUCUCAGCUCCCUCCCUAGCAAACUCUGUGUCUGUUACGUGUAACCCCUACCCACCCUAAAUCCCAUCCCUGCAAAAGAACCCCACUCUCCACACUUAGGAAGCAAACAGAUAAACUAGAUUAUUUCCUCAUUGGAAAUUUAGAUUUGACUUUUCCAGAGGCACCUGCACCUUUAUUAUUAUUUAUUUAUUUAUUUAUUUAUUUAGAGAAAGGAUCUCACUUUGUCAUCCAGGCUGGAGUGCAGUGGUGUGACCAAGGCUCCCUGCAGCCUCAAUCUCUCAACCUUAAGUGAUCCUCCCAUUUCAGCCUCUCGAAUAGCUGGGACUACAGGCGUGCACCACCACACCCAGCUAAUUUUUGCAUUCUUUGUAAAAAUGGGGUCUCACUAUGUCGCCAGGGCUGGUCUCAAACUCCUGAGCGCAAGCCAUCCUCCUGCCUUUGCCUCCCAAAGUGUUGGGAUUACAGGCAUGAGCCAUUAUGCCCUGCUGCAUCUGCACUUUAAUAUUGGAUUCUUGAAGAGUGAGAAAGAUAUCAAAAUUCAGUGACUCUCAUCAUUGCCUCUCAGGCACUAGGGCCACCCCUAUGUUCCAUUUUUAGGUGGUGAGCCUCUCUGAAUCUGCAAAUUCAUAUCACUUUGGUCACAACCUAUUCAGCUAGCUAUGUGGCCUUAGGAAAAUCACUGACUUCUCUGAAUCGCAUUAACUCAUCUGCAGAAUGUGAAUAACAAUAGUACCCCCAUUUAUUGGGUUGUUGUAAAGCUUAGAUGGGAUUAUCUAUUACAGCCCUAAGCACUAUGCGUGGCACAUAGCCAAGAUGCAAUUAAUGUUAGGGAUUAUCAUCAUCAUCAUUAUUUUUACUCUAAUCUGUCAUAACCCAAUUCGCUCAUUCAAGAACUAUUUAUUGAGCACCUGCUAUGUGCCAGGCAUUGUCCUUGACCCUGAGAGUAGGGCAGUGAAGGAGUCAUACAAGGUUCCUGCCUUCUAGGGGCUUACAUUCUAGUACAAAUGUACCACACCUUUCUGUUUGAUAAGCACUUUCUUCCCCAUUGUGUCAUGUUGUUCUCACUAAUGCCUUUCAAUCAGGCAAAGGCGGUAUGAUUGUCCGCAUUGUACAGAUAGAAAGCUGAGGCUUAGAGAAUUAAGCUAACAGAGAUAGCUAGAAAGUGGCCAGGUACAACUUGAUCUAGGGUCCUCCUGGCUCGUUUCUGUGCUCUCUCAUGAUGGACACUGAUGAUUGUUUUGGGGUGAGGGGCAUGGAAGCAGCUCUCAGAGCCUUGAGAGCUCUGACCCACCAGCAGAAGCACAAAAGAGAACCAGGGACUGGCUUUGGUUCGAUUGCGAGUGUCCCAGUUAGUUCUGUCCAUGAAGUCUGUCAAUGACUGGGCCUAACAAUGUGUGCCUCUGCCCGGUGUCAGCCUUGGGGGCCUGGAGGAGACUUUAUCUUAAGGAAAAAGUGCUUGCUUCAGCACAUGGCCAGUGGGGCCUGGCUGUGACAGCAGGCAGCUCUGCUGUGGCAGCUCAGCUGUCUGAGAGCACUUCCCCUUGGGUUCCCCGCAGAGCAGGAGAGAAGGUGUCUAGGCCUAUGGGCUUGGUGACCAAACUGCAUGGUUUCUGGUAGUGUGCCUGGAACUCCUGCUGUGCAAGAUUUCCUAUAUACACCCAGCAUCCGCCUAGUCUGGGCUGGGCGGGGCAGGGCUGAUCCUGUCUGAGAACACAGGAACUGGAAGUCUGUACCGGGGCAGGUGGCAGGGGCAGGCCUGGCAAAGACCCAGGGAGAGGACACCAAGGGCCAGCCACCGCACAGAGAGACCAGUGACUGAACAUGGCUGGGCCGGGGUGUUUCCCAGCCCCGUCACAGUGAAAACUCACCCGUACCCGGUGACCCCAGGUGACAAUUCUGAACCUGCAACAGCAGUGCAUAACUGAUAGUGUCACCUCUGCCUAAUCCUCCUGGAAACACACACACACCCUGCUUUAUUUCCCGUCUCUCAACACCCUUCCUUAUGGGUACUUCAUACCAGUCCCAAGAGCAGGCUUUUGUUUACUUUUUCUUUUUUUUUUUUUUUUGAGAUGGAGUCUUCCUCUGUCGCCCAGGCUGGAGUGCAAUGGUGUGAUCUUGGCUCACUGAAACCUCUGCCUCCCGGGUUCAAGUGAUUCUCCUCCCCCAGCCUCCUGAGUAGCUGGAAUUACAGGCAUGCACCACCACACCCCACUAAUUUUGUAUUUUUAGUAGAUACAGGGUUUCGCCACGUUGGUCAGGUUGGUUUUGAACUCCUGACCUCAGGUGAUCUGCCCGCCUCAGUCUCCCAAAGUGCUGGGAUUACAGGCGUGAGCCACCGCGCCCGGCCUUGUUUUCCUUUUUACUGAAUUUAAGUGCUUAGGGUUAUUCACAAUAUUUGACUCAUGACAUUCUUUCAUCUUCAGUUGGACCUUGUGCAACCUGCAUCUGGUAAUUUGUUAUUUAUCUGUUUGUGUAUUUCCUUAUAAUACAGUCACUCCACUGCACGUUCUUCCCCUGUGUCCUCCCUUCCUAUUACUUUGCCUUCCCCACCCUAUUCUGAAUAUUGAGUUCAUCAUUCCUUUGCUCCUCUAAAAACUAAUGCUUUUUCAAAUAUUUUUCUAAAAGCCAUAUUGUUUAGAUUUGUUGUUUUUUCUUGUGUAAAGGAAUAUCCUGGCUAGGCGCAGUGGUUCAUACCUAUAAUAUCAGCACUUUGGGAGGGGGAGGCAGGAGGAUCACUUGAAGCCAGGAGUUCAAGACCAGCCUGGGCAACACAGCAAGACCCUGUCUCUACAAAAAAAUUUUUAAAAUGUAGCUGGGCGUGGUGGUGUGUGCCUGUAGUCCCAGCUACUUGGGAGGCUGAGGCAGGAGGAUUGCUUGAGCCCAGGAGAUUGAGGCUGCAGUGAGCCAUGAUAGUGCCACUGCACUCCAACUUGGGCAACAGAGCAAGACCCUGUCUCUAAAAAAAAAAAUUAAAAUUAAAACAAAAAAGAAUAUCCUGCUAUAUGCAGCUUUCUUGGGUAUACUUUUUUCUCAUAAUAUUAUGUGGCUAAAACUCACCCAUAGCGUAGCAUUCAGCUACGGUCCACUUGUUGUCCCUGCUCUAUUGCAGUUCUCCCUAGUAUGUUCCAUGGGAAUUUACUGAAUCUCCUGUUAGUGGACAUUUGGGUUGUUACCAGCUUUCCAUGACUUUGAACACGCUAAGCUGAUCAUUUUUGUCUGUGUCUCCAGGGAAACAAUGUGAAUUUAUCAAUUUACAAUCCCAGUAACAACAAACAUAUAAAUAUCCAAUUGAUCUGUGUUCUUUCCAACAAUUUGGUAUUAUCAAGCUUCUUAAUUUUUUCCAACUGAAAGGGUAUUAAGUGACAUCUCAUUGUGAUCUCUUCAUGGUUAUUGCCUUUCCAAAUAUGGUUUACAGUGGUCAGUUGGUGGAGCAGUGGGGGUCAUCCUGCAAGGGGACUGUGAAGAUUUUUUUUUUUUUUUUUUAGAGAUAGGGUCUCUAAAACUCAGGCUGGAUUGAGUUCAGUGGCACAAUCAUGGGUCACUGCAGCCUCAACUUCCUGGGCUCAAGCGAUCCUCCCACCUCAGCCUCCCAAAGUGUUGAGAUUACCAGCAUGAGCCACUAUGCCCAGCCAAGACGUAAGGAUUUAAUGAAGCACAGAAUGCUUGCAAAGCCUUUCCCAGUUAGGACCACGUCACUGUCUUAUUCAACUUUGGGUCGCCAAUACCCAACACAAUGCCGGGUACCUCAUCAUUAUUAAACCAACAAUAUGAUAAUAUUAGGUUGGUGCAAAAAUAAUUGCGAUUUUUGCCAUAACAUUUAUUGAGUGCUUGCUUAUUAAGUGCCAGGUGCUAUAUUAACUGACACCUUUACUUUUAUUAUUUCAUUUAAUUAUUCUGGAAACUCUAUAAGUUAAGUUCUAUACUACCCCAAUUUUGUAGAUGGGAAACUGAAACUAAGUGUCUCUCCCAGAAUCACACAAGUAGUAAAUGAUAGAGCCAGGAUCUGAACGCUGGCAUCUGACACCUAAGUCCUUAGCUACUAUAUUAUAGGUGCUCAAUAAAUUCUUGAAUGAAAUAACUUCACUGUGUUAUUCUCUUUCAUGUUGCUUAUAACCAAACACUUGAAACUGGAUAAUUGAUAAAGAAAAGAAAUUUCUUCACAGUUACAGAGGCUGAGAAGUCCCAGGUCAAGGGGUCCUAUCUGGUGACAGCCUUCUUGCUUGAGGGGACUCUCUGAAGAGUACUAAGGUGGUCCAAGGUGUCGCAUGGUGAGGGGGCUGAGUGUGCUAACAUGUUAGCUCAGGUCUUUGUUCUUCUUAUAAAGCCAUCAGUCCCCACCCAUUAUAACCCAUUAAUCCAUGAGUGGAUUAAUCCACUCAUGGAUUAACCCAUUCAUUAGGGCAGAGCCCUCAUGAUGCAAGCACCGUUUAAAGACCACAUCUCUCAAUACUGCCACAUUGGGGAUUAAAGUUCAACAUGAGUUUUAGAGGAGACAAAUAUUCAACCCACAGCACCUACCCAUAACCAGAGAUAGGGUCACAUGCCAUGGUACUUUUACUUUUUAUCUCUUAUCAAGUAUAUUUAAAUACACUUACAUUUUGAUUAUAAACAUGGCUUAAAGAAUUUAACUCAAUUUAUAAUUGGUUAUAAUUUCUCAGCAAUCAUGCAGACUUGAGAACUCUCGCUGUGAGAGAUAUCUAACUCACAGAUUAUUCUGAAAUGCCAAUUCCUCCUUUAUCAACAAUUCCUCUAACCUCGCUCUCCCUUCCUUCCUUCCUUCCUUCCUUCCUUCCUUCCUUCCUUCCUUCCUUCCUUCUUUCUCUUUCUUUCACAGUCUUGCUCUGUCACCCAGGCUGGAGUGCCUGGGUGACGAUCAUAGCUCACUGCAGCCUCAAACUCCUAGGCUCAAGCAAUCAGCCCCCAUCAGCCUCCCAAAGCACUGGGAUUACAGGCAUGAGCCACCGUACCUGGUCUGUUGUGUCUAUUAUUGACCCACAAGGGCAGAGAUAUUUGUAUGCUUAGUUUUGUCUGUAUCUUUAGUGAAUUUAGCACUUAAUGUGUCCCUAGUACCUGUAACUGUGUGUGGCACAGAGAGGUAACUCAACAAAUAUUUAUUGAAUGAAGAAAUAAAUGCAUGCUUGCAGGAAUGGAUGAAUAAGUGAAUGAAUCAAUGAAUACUAAAUUGAAUAGUUAAUGAAAAUUGACGAUAUUAUUUUGAUUUUGUGGUUUUUAAAAAUUUUGGAACCAGGCUGGGUGCGGUGGCUCACACUGUAAUCCCAGCACUUUGGGAGGCCGAGAUGGGUGGAUGACCUUAGGUCAGGAGUUCGAGCCCAGCCUGGCCAAAAUGGUGAAACCCUGUCUCUACUAAAAAUACAAAAAUUAGCCAGGUGUGGUGGCAGGUGCCUGUAAUCCCAGCUACUCAGGAGGUUGAGGCAGGAGAAUCACUUGAACCCAGGAGGUGGAGGUUGCAGUGAGCCGAGAUCGUGCCAUUGCACUCCAGCCUGGGGGACAAGAGCGAGACUUCGUCUCAAAAAAAAAAUUGGAACCAACUGUUUUUUCAGGUUUCAGACAUUUCUGUAAACCAGUAGAAAAGCUGGGAGGCAGACAGGCGUGGUGGCUUACGCCUGUAAUCCCAGCACUUUGGGAGGCCGAGGCGGGUGGAUCACCUGAGGUCAGGAGUUCAAGACCAGCCUGGCCAACAUGGUGAAACCUCGUCUCUACUAAAAAUACAAAAAUAAGCUGGGCAUGGUGUUGGGCAUCUGUAAUCCCAGCUAUUUGGGAGGCUGAGGCAGGAGAAUUGCUUGAACCCAGGAGGUGGAGGUUGCAGUGAGCUGAUAUGGCUCUGCCCCACUCCAGCCUGGGCAACAGAGUGAGACUCCGUCUCAAAAAAAAAAAAAAAAAGAAAGAAAGAAAAGCUGGGAGGCCUGAGAUUUUGUGUCUAUUAUACCUAAGGGAUGAAAGAGUCCUGACCUGGAGACCCGAAACAAUGUUUGGCUGCUUUUUUCUUUGUCUCUUGUAAACCAACAUCAGCAAUGAGCAGGCCACCUCAAGUGUGACUCAAUCAACGCGAGGCAGGAGGCAUGCAAAACAAAACAGAAAACUCCUGGCAGCCUUAAUAUAGCGAUUUUUCUAGCAAUCUACAUGACUAUCCAGGCCCAAUGCACCCCAUUACAUAUGCAAAACAUCUGACGUUUGUGUAACAAGCCCUUAACCCCUGGCUGUUAUUCUUAUUUCCAAACUGGGGUGCAUCAUUAGAUAAAUGCAGAAAUCAAGAACCGUCGCUCCUAGUCAAGCGUCUGUGGCUCAGUUCUCAGAGCCAGGCCAAAGGAGUAAUUAUAGCUUUCCUCUAUAGUGUACGGGGCAGGAGGCUGAUUUAAUAAAGGAAGCCUACUGUCUGUCUCCAGCCUGGCUCUGACUCAUGGAACGAGGGAGUCCCAGAGCACUACCCACAGAGGGUGGGUGGUGAGCAGCUGAGGGUGGGAGGUGAGGGUGGCCGCUAGCAAGGCCUGGGCCCAGAGCCCUGAGAAUGAGGAAACUCCCUGCUUGGCCAGGAGGAACCUGCAGCUGGAGCCAGAGGAAGUGAGGCUCAGACAGAGCAGCUGCUGUUCCAGCAACAGCAGCAACUGCCGCACCCUUGAAAGGAGGCCCCUGCCGUGUGGACCCGUAAAAUAAAAUGGGAUUUUGACACUUCAUGACAUGUCAUUAUUUAGAGCAAUAAUGAAUAUUGACCUGUUUUGGAUUAGUUGAUGACCUUCGGAAAUGAUCCAAUAAUAUCUACUAUAGAGAAGCUGAAUAUACUCCAUUUGGAGUGAACAGCCCGGAUUGUUACAGAAUUUUCAAGAUGACAGAUCCAAUGAUGGACUUUUUUGAUGAUGCCAAUCUUUUUGGUGAGACCUUAGAAGGUUUGUCAGAUGAUGCAUUUGUACAACCAGGACCUGUUUCACUAGUUGAUGAAUUGAAUUUGGGUGCAGAAUUUGAACCGUUGCACAUAGAUUCACUGAACCAUGUUCAAGGUACUCCAACACAUCAGAAGAUGACUGAUUUUGAACAGUUAAAUCAAUUUGAUUCAAUAAAAUUUCACCAUGUUAAUCAAUCUUUUGGUAGCCCAGCUGAACAUGUGUUAUCUCCACACUCUCAGUUUAAUUGUUCUCCAAUCCAUCCCCAAAACCAACCCAAUGGUUUGUUUCCAGAUGUAUCAGAUGGCAGUCCAAUGUGGGGCCAUCAGACAGCUACUACCAUUUCAAAUCAAAAUGGAUCUCCUUUUCACCAACAAGGACAUUCACACUCUAUGCAUCAAAAUAAAAGCUUUGUGGCACACCAUGACUUUGCCUUAUUUCAGGCCAAUGAACAACAAACACAGUGUACUUCACUACGCUCACAACAAAACAGAAAUAAUCUCAACCCAGGGCAGAAUUCUCUUAGCCAGUCUAAAAAUUUUAUGAAUGUUUCUGGUCCACAUAGAGUCAAUGUUAACCACCCACCACAGAUGACUAAUGCAUCUAAUUCACAACAGUCUAUUUCAAUGCAGCAAUUUUCUCAAACGUCAAAUCCUUCAGCACACUUCCACAAGUGUAGCAGUCAUCAAGAAGGAAAUUUUAAUGGACCUUCCCCAAAUAUGACUUCUUGUUCUGUCAGUAAUUCACAGCAAUUUUCUUCACAUUAUUCCUUUUCCAGUAAUCAUAUAUCACCAAACAGUCUACUUCAGUCCUCUGCAGUUCUUGCAUCUAAUCAUACAAAUCAGACUUUAUCUGAUUUUACUGGAAGUAAUUCCUUUUCACCUCAUAGAGGAAUCAAGCAAGAAUCUACUCAGCAUAUCCUAAACCCCAAUACAUCAUUGAAUUCAAAUAAUUUCCAAAUAUUGCAUUCAUCACAUCCUCAGGGUAAUUAUAGCAAUUCAAAAUUAUCUCCUGUGCACAUGAACUUCCCAGAUCCUGUUGACUCAGGAACUCAAAUGGGCCAUUUCAAUGAUCAUGUAGAAACUAAUGGCUUUUCAUCUUUAGAAGAGAAUUUACUUCAUCAAGUGGAAUCUCAAACUGAGCCAUUCACAGGACUUGACCCCGAGGACCUCCUUCAGGAGGGUCUUCUUCCUCACUUUGAUGAGUCAACAUUCGGACAAGAUAAUUCAAGUCACAUUUUAGAUCAUGACCUUGAUCGGCAGUUUACUUCGCAUCUGGUAACACGGCCUUCUGAUAUGGCUCAGACUCAGUUGCAAAGUCAGGCUCGGAGUUGGCAUUCAUCAUUUUCUAAUCAUCAGCAUUUACAUGACAGAAAUCACCUAUGUUUACAGCGACAGCACUGCCUGGGGUGGUGAAAAAGCAGAGGGCAAGCCUUUGUCUGACGCCAAAAAUGUCUUCAGUGAAGAGGCCAAGAGGAAGGCCUCCAUCUUCCAAGAAGAGCGAUGGUUCUGGGACAUAUACUAAGUUGCAGAAUACCCAGGUGAGGGUCAUGUCUGAGAAGAAGCAGAGAAAAAAGGUGGAAUCAGAAAGCAAGCAAGAAAAGGCUAAUCGUAUAAUAUCAGAGGCCAUAGCAAAAGCAAAGGAGCGUGGGGAACGCAAUAUUCCACGAGUAAUGAGCCCUGAAAACUUUCCUACUGCUUCAGUUGAAGGAAAAGAGGAAAAGAAAGGUAGAAGGAUGAAAUCCAAGCCAAAGGACAAAGACAGCAAAAAAACAAAAACAUGUUCUAAGUUAAAAGAGAAGACAAAAAUUGGCAAACUCAUUAUUACAUUGGGUAAGAAACAAAAAAGAAAGAAUGAGUCUUCAGAUGAAAUAUCUGAUGCAGAACAGAUGCCACAGCAUACAUUAAAAGAUCAAGACUCUCAAAAAAGAAGAUCAAAUCGACAAAUUAAAAGAAAAAAAUACGCAGAAGAUAUAGAAGGGAAGCAAUCUGAAGAAGAGGUUAAAGGUUCUAUGAAAAUAAAAAAGAAUUCAGCUCCUUUACCUGGUGAACAGCCUUUACAAUUGUUUGUGGAGAAUCCGAGUGAAGAAGAUGCUGCAAUUGUAGACAAAAUUCUAUCUUCUAGAACCGUAAAAAAGGAAAUAUCACCUGGAGUGAUGAUUGAUACAGAAGAAUUUUUUGUAAAAUACAAGAAUUACUCCUAUCUUCACUGUGAGUGGGCCACAGAAGAGCAGCUUUUGAAAGAUAAAAGGAUCCAGCAGAAAAUCAAACGAUUCAAAUUGAGACAAGCACAAAGAGCACAUUUUUUUGCAGACAUGGAAGAAGAACCAUUUAACCCAGACUACGUUGAAGUAGACAGAGUAUUAGAAGUCUCUUUUUGUGAAGAUAAGGAUACUGGUGAGCCUGUUAUUUACUACUUAGUAAAAUGGUGCUCAUUGCCAUAUGAAGAUAGUACUUGGGAACUAAAAGAAGAUGUAGAUCUUGCAAAAAUAGAAGAGUUUGAACAACUGCAAGCUUCAAGGCCUGACACAAGACGUUUGGACCGUCCUCCUUCUAAUAUUUGGAAGAAAAUAGAUCAAUCCAGGGACUAUAAAAAUGGCAAUCAACUCAGGGAAUAUCAACUGGAAGGACUCAACUGGCUCUUGUUCAAUUGGUACAAUAGACGAAACUGCAUCUUAGCAGAUGAAAUGGGUCUUGGCAAAACUAUUCAAUCAAUUACAUUCCUCUAUGAAAUCCUUCUGACUGGUAUAAGAGGACCUUUCCUGAUUAUUGCUCCACUUUCUACUAUUGCAAACUGGGAGAGAGAAUUUCGUACGUGGACUGAUAUUAACGUUGUGGUUUAUCAUGGGAGCCUGAUUAGCAGACAAAUGAUACAGCAAUACGAGAUGUACUUCAGGGAUUCACAGGGGCGUAUCAUUCGAGGAGCUUACAGAUUCCAAGCCAUCAUCACCACUUUUGAAAUGAUUCUUGGAGGCUGUGGAGAGCUUAAUGCAAUUGAAUGGCGAUGUGUGAUUAUUGAUGAAGCACAUAGGUUAAAAAAUAAAAAUUGUAAACUCUUAGAGGGCCUGAAACUCAUGAAUCUGGAACACAAGGUGCUUUUGACUGGCACCCCUCUCCAAAAUACAGUUGAAGAACUAUUUAGUCUUCUUCACUUUCUUGAACCCUUAAGGUUUCCUUCUGAAUCAACAUUUAUGCAAGAAUUUGGGGAUCUGAAAACAGAGGAACAGGUACAGAAACUUCAGGCUAUCCUGAAACCAAUGAUGUUGAGACGAUUAAAAGAAGAUGUGGAAAAGAAGUUGGCACCUAAAGAAGAAACCAUCAUUGAAGUAGAACUUACUAAUAUUCAAAAGAAAUACUACCGGGCUAUCUUGGAAAAGAACUUUUCUUUUUUAUCCAAAGGAGCAGGACAAACUAAUGUACCUAACUUGGUCAAUACCAUGAUGGAGCUCAGGAAAUGUUGUAAUCAUCCAUAUCUUAUAAAAGGUGCUGAGGAGAAAAUACUUGGAGAAUUUAGAGAUACUUACAAUCCAGCUGCUUCUGAUUUUCAUCUUCAAGCAAUGAUCCAGUCUGCUGGUAAAUUGGUCCUUAUUGAUAAAUUGCUUCCCAAAAUGAAAGCCGGAGGUCAUAAAGUGCUCAUCUUCUCUCAAAUGGUUCGUUGCCUUGACAUUCUGGAGGACUAUCUCAUACAUAAAAGAUACUUAUAUGAGCGAAUUGAUGGCAGAGUCAGAGGAAAUCUUCGGCAAGCUGCUAUAGAUAGAUUUAGUAAACCUGAUUCAGAUAGAUUUGUUUUUCUCCUGUGUACCCGAGCUGGUGGGUUGGGCAUCAACUUAACUGCAGCUGAUACAUGUAUAAUUUUUGAUUCUGAUUGGAAUCCUCAGAAUGAUCUUCAGGCCCAAGCUCGUUGCCACAGAAUUGGUCAGAACAAAGCAGUUAAAGUCUACAGACUGGUAACUCGUAACUCAUAUGAGAGAGAGAUGUUUGACCGAGCCAGUUUGAAACUGGGCCUAGAUAAAGCUGUGUUACAGAGCAUGAGUGGAAGAGAAAGUAAUGUUGGUGGUAUUCAGCAGCUUUCCAAAAAGGAAAUAGAAGAUCUGCUUCGAAGAGGUGCUUAUGGUGCUAUUAUGGAGGAAGAAGAUGAAGGCUCUAAAUUCUGCGAAGAGGAUAUCGAUCAGAUUUUACUACGUCGUACAAAAACUAUUACAAUUGAAUCAGAAGGACGUGGGUCAACAUUUGCCAAGGCGAGUUUUGUGGCAUCUGGAAACCGGACAGAUAUUUCUUUAGAUGAUCCCAACUUCUGGCAAAAAUGGGCUAAAAAGGCAGAAAUAGAUAUAGAGGCCAUCAGUGGCAGAAACAGCUUGGUUAUUGACACUCCAAGAAUUAGGAAGCAAACAAGACCUUUUAGUGCCACAAAAGAUGAAUUGGCUGAAUUAUCUGAAGCUGAAAGUGAAGGAGAUGAAAAGCCCAAACUCCGGAGACCCUGUGACCGUUCCAAUGGCUAUGGAAGAACUGAAUGCUUUAGAGUUGAGAAAAACCUGCUAGUUUAUGGGUGGGGCCGAUGGAGAGAGAUUCUAUCUCAUGGCCGUUUCAAAAGGCAGCUAAAUGAACACGAUGUAGAGAUAAUUUGCCGAGCUCUCUUAGCAUAUUGCCUUGUUCACUACCGAGGAGAUGAGAAGAUUAAAGGUUUCAUAUGGGAUCUCAUUACUCCAACUGAAGAUGGACAGACACGAGAGCUACAGAAUCAUCUAGGCCUAUCAGCUCCUGUACCCAGGGGUCGAAAAGGGAAGAAAGUAAAAACUCAAACAAGCUCAUUUGAUAUACAAAAAGCAGAAUGGCUUCGAAAAUAUAAUCCCGAGCAGCUCCUUCAAGAUGAAGGCUACAAAAAACAUAUAAAACACCACUGUAAUAAGGUUUUGCUUCGUGUGAGAAUGCUGUAUUAUCUAAAGCAAGAAGUUAUUGGAAAUGAGUGUCAGAAAGUAUUUGAUGGAGUUGAUGCAAGUGACAUUGAUGUUUGGGUACCAGAACCAGACCACUCAGAAGUUCCUGCUGAGUGGUGGGAUUUUGAUGCUGAUAAGUCACUCCUUAUUGGAGUUUUUAAACAUGGAUAUGAAAAAUAUAACACUAUUCGAGCAGACCCAGCAUUAUGCUUCUUGGAAAGAGUGGGAAAACCUGAUGAGAAAGCAGUUGCUGCUGAACAGAGAGCGAAUGAUUAUAUGGAUGGGGAUGUGGAAGAUCCAGAAUACAAACCUGCCCCAGCCAUCUUUAAAGAUGAUAUAGAGGAUGAUGUUUCCUCACCAGGAGAUCUUGUUAUAGCAGAUGGAGAUGGUCAACUGAUGGAGGGUGAUAAAGUAUAUUGGCCUACUCAAUCAGCUUUAACCACACGUUUGAGGCGUCUCAUCACUGCAUACCAGCGUACUAAUAAAAACAGACAAAUUCAGCAGAUACAACCGACUUUCUCGGUGCCUACCAGUGUAAUGCAGCCUAUUUAUGAGGAAGCCACUCUUAAUCCUAAAAUGGCAGCCAAGAUAGAAAGACAGCAAAGAUGGACAAGAAGAGAAGAAGCUGACUUUUAUAGGGUUGUAUCUACAUUUGGAGUGGUUUUUGACCCUGACAGAGGCCAAUUUGAUUGGACAAAAUUUAGAGCUAUGGCUAGGCUACAUAAGAAAACUGAUGAUAGUUUGGAAAAAUAUUUGUACGCAUUCAUGUCCAUGUGUCGGAGGGUUUGUCGUCUUCCUUCCAAAGAAGAAUUGGUGGAUCCAAAUAUUUUUAUCCAGCCCAUCACAGAAGAACGUGCUUCUAGGACUUUGUAUCGCAUUGAACUUCUAAGGAAAGUACGGGAACAGGCCCUUCGACAUCCACAGUUGUUUGAACGCUUGAAGCUUUGCCAUCCAAAUCCAGAUUUACCAGUCUGGUGGGAAUGUGGCCCUCAUGAUAGGGAUUUGCUUAUUGGUGCUGCCAAACACGGGGUGAGCCGAACAGACUAUCACAUUCUUCGUGAUCCUGAACUCUCAUUUAUGGCAGCUCAGAGGAACUACAGUCAAAGUAAGAUGGCUCAUUCAAGGACUUCUACCCCACUUCUACAGCAAUAUCAAGUAGCACUUUCUGCUUCUCCUCUUACCUCUCUACCUAGGCUCCUAGAUGCUAAAGGUAUUAUUCUAGAGGAGAUGAAAGUUAAAAGUGAAAACCUUAAAGAGGAGCCUCAGUCUUCUGAAGAAGAAUCUAUGUCUUCUGUGGAAACCAGGACACUAAUAAAAUCUGAGCCUGUAAGUCCAAAGAAUGGUGUUUUACCACAGGCUACUGGAGACCAGAAAUCUGGUGGAAAAUGUGAAACAGACAGACGCAUGGUUGCAGCCAGAACAGAACCCCUAACUCCAAACCCAGCUUCUAAGAAACCAAGAGUCCACAAAAGGGGAUCAGAAUCUAGUUCUGAUUCUGACUCAGAUUCUGAGAGAUCAUCUUGUUCUUCCAGAUCAUCUUCUUCCUCAUCAUCCUCUUCUUGCUCCCACUCUCGAUCAGGCUCUAGUUCUUCUUCAUCUUCAUCUUGUUCUUCAGCAUCUUCUUCAUCCUCUUCCUCCACCUCUUCCUCCUCCUCCUCCUCUUCAUCUUCAUCAGAAGAAAGUGACAGUGAUGAAGAAGAAGCCCAAAAACGAGCAGAAAGUACUACUCACAUGAAAGCCUAUGAUGAAGAAAGCGUCGCGUCACUGAGCACUACCCAGGAUGAGACUCAGGAUAGUUUUCAGAUGAACAAUGGGACACCAGAGUCUGCUUAUAUCUUACAAGGUGGAUAUAUGCUGGCAGCCUCGUAUUGGCCAAAGGAUCGUGUGAUGAUCAAUAGGUUGGACAGUAUUUGUCAAACAGUUCUGAAAGGAAAGUGGCCUUCAGCUAGAAGAAGUUAUGAUGCUAACACAGUGGCUUCUUUCUAUACCACAAAACUGCUGGACAGCCCUGGAGCAGCUACAGAAUACAGCGAUCCCAGUGUACCCACUCCCCCAGGUGCCGGUGUUAAAGAAGAACAUGAUCAGUCAACACAGAUGUCAAAGGUGAAGAAGCAUGUACGAGAAAAGGAGUUUACAGUGAAAAUCAAAGACGAAGGUGGUUUGAAGUUGACAUUUCAGAAGCAAGGGCUUGCUCAGAAAAGACCAUUUGAUGGUGAAGACGGUGCUCUGGGGCAGCAGCAGUACCUCACUCGGCUUCGAGAGCUUCAAAGUGCAUCAGAGACCAGCCUCGUCAAUUUCCCAAAAUCCAUACCAGUAUCAGGUACUUCCAUUCAACCAACCCUUGGUGCCAAUGGUGUGAUAUUAGACAACCAGCCUAUAGUCAAAAAAAGGCGAGGAAGGAGGAAGAAUGUAGAAGGUGUUGACAUCUUCUUUUUUAACAGAAAUAAACCACCUAAUCAUGUUUCUUUAGGCUUAACCUCCUCACAGAUUUCCACAGGGAUAAAUCCAGCACUAUCCUAUACUCAACCUCAAGGAAUUCCUGAUACAGAAAGUCCAGUUCCAGUUAUUAAUCUUAAAGAUGGAACGAGACUUGCAGGAGAUGAUGCACCAAAGAGAAAGGAUUUGGAAAAAUGGCUUAAGGAGCACCCGGGUUAUGUGGAAGAUUUGGGAGCUUUUAUUCCUAGAAUGCAGCUUCAUGAGGGAAGACCCAAACAAAAAAGACACCGUUGCAGAAACCCCAAUAAACUAGAUGUGAAUAGUCUCACUGGAGAAGAACGUGUUCAACUGAUUAACAGAAGAAAUGCUAGAAAGGUUGGAGGUGCAUUUGCUCCCCCUUUGAAAGAUUUAUGUAGAUUCCUAAAAGAAAAUUCAGAAUAUGGAGUAGCUCCUGAAUGGGGAGAUGUUGUUAAGCAAUCUGGAUUUCUUCCAGAAAGCAUGUAUGAACGUAUUCUCACUGGUCCCGUUGUGAGAGAGGAAGUAAGCAGGCGGGGGAGACGGCCUAAAAGUGGAAUUGCAAAGGCCACAGCAGCAGCAGCUGCUGCAUCUGCCACCAGUGUUUCAGGCAAUCCUUUGUUAGCCAAUGGACUACUUCCAGGUGUGGAUCUCACAACUCUUCAGGCCUUACAACAAAACCUACAAAACUUGCAGUCACUGCAAGUAACUGCUGGGUUGAUGGGAAUGCCUACCGGCCUUCCUUCUGGAGGAGAAGCUAAAAACAUGGCUGCUAUGUUCCCCAUGCUGCUGUCAGGAAUGGCUGGAUUACCAAAUCUGUUGGGCAUGGGAGGACUCCUGACAAAGCCUACGGAAUCUGGGACAGAAGACAAAAAGGGAAGUGACUCUAAGGAGUCAGAAGGAAAAACAGAAAGGACAGAGAGCCAAAGUUCAGAGAAUGGUGGAGAAAACUCUGUGUCAAGUUCUCCUUCCACAUCCUCUACUGCUGCAUUAAAUACAGCUGCAGCUGCCAACCCAUUAGCUCUUAACCCACUAUUACUAUCUAAUAUACUUUAUCCAGGGAUGCUUCUCACUCCAGGCCUUAAUCUUCAUAUUCCAACUUUGUCCCAGUCCAAUACUUUUGAUGUACAAAACAAAAACAGUGACUUAGGCUCGUCUAAGUCUGUAGAAGUAAAAGAAGAAGAUUCCAGAAUUAAAGAUCAGGAAGACAAAGGAGGAACUGAACCAAGUCCUCUCAAUGAAAACAGCACAGAUGAGGGUUCAGAGAAAGCUGAUGCUUCAUCUGGAUCUGAUAGUACAUCGUCGUCAUCUGAGGAUUCAGAUUCUAGUAAUGAAGACUGAUUCCCAGACUCUGCACUUAAAAUAUGAACUGAUUUUGGAUUUUUUCUUUAAUAAUUAAUUGUAAAUACCCCAGUGUUGAGUGCAUCAAUAACUUACUGACCGAACAUUUCAGUUAUUUGUUUAGAAGUGCAAACUGCUUUCAGAGACUUUUUGCAUGUAAUAUUUCUUAAGAUUCAUAAGUUUCUGAACUCGUAUGUACUAUCAAAUACAUAAAGGUGUAAAAUUACAACAAAAGGCAUUAUAAUUUUGUUGGGGGUUAAUUUUAUGAAAAUUAUGCUCAAUAAGAGUUGUAUAUUUAAUAUAUUUGCAGUGAACACAGAAUACUUUAUGCAUAUUACUGAUUUAAUUUGAAUAUAGUUUUACAGCCUCCUUGACACCUAUAAUUUACAGAUCAAAACUCAGCAAUAAUUUGGGCAGCUAAUGAAUGUCAUGAAAGCUGUAGAAUCUACAUCACCAUCCAUUGCUUUAAUUACAUGAAAAUGCUCUAGUGUUGUGAUGCACUGCUGAUGUUUCCAAUUCAGGUACAAGUAUGUUUUAAAGAAGAAAUAAGUUUCCCAAUCAGCCAAUUUAACUGGCUACCUGUUACCUCAGCUGAGUUAGUUUAGGAAGUUUACAUUCGUUUCUAAUUCUAUACUUGUUUUCAGGGGUUUUUUAAACACAUCCUAUAUAUCAUGUCAAUCUGGCAAGAAAUAUGACUUGCUUUUUGCUGAGCUUAAUUCAGAUAUCAGUAAAAUUAAGUCAUAAAAUAAUCAUGUGUCAUGUGACUUUGGCACCCUAUAGACAUACUUAGUUUUAACUUUUCAAAGUUUGGCCUCCUAUUAGAAAUAAUCAUGUCUCAGAUGAGUAAUGUCUGUUUCCAGGGUUCAGAAAAGGCAAACUCAUGAAAUGCCACUGAAAAGAACUUUCAACACAGCAUACUUCAUGUAAAAGAAAUUGUUUGUUUGCUUUCUUUGUGUAGAUUUCUAUUUGUGUUUUAUGUCAUGGAAAUAUUCCAGAAUUAACAGAUAAUAGUGGUAAAGUAAUAUGCAGAUAGUCUAAAUUCAUUUUGAGUUUCUAGGUGUAAGCAGACUAAAUGUUGCCCAGAAUCAGUGUUGGGUUAUCAGUUUAUAUUAAAUAUACUGAGUUGCCCGUUUUGAAAAUGCACUUUGAAUAAUCUCAAAAAGAUGUACAAGUUAUACCUGUAAACCACAAAAGUGAAGCCUGAGGCUUCUGUUCAAUUUCAUAGACUCCUUUACCAUGUAAAAUUUGUCUGAUAUUUGAUUUGUGAUACAAUUUCUCCUGCUAAAGCUGCUAUUAUUCUGACAAGGUAGAGGUCCAGGUUCACCUUUAUAUAUAUUUAAAACAAUUAGUACUGAAUUGGACAUAAAAAUAUUGACAUUCUAAGGAGAGAUAUAUGUUAGCAUUUUUCUGGUACUCAAAUAAGUUAGUAGUAAAGUCUGCAAGGGCAUAAAUUUAGGGGGAAAAAGUGUCCCAGUUCUCUCCUACAGAAAAAAUACUUUCAGUAUGUUUUGAUAAAACUGUUGCUUUGUCAUGAGUUAGUCAAUUGUAUCAGGUUUUCCAAGACCUUUACCAGUAAAUUAUGUUUCUGUAUGUAAAAUAACCCCUUAUUAGAGAGACAGUGUUAUAUGUAUUUACAAAAUUAUAUAAGUUCCAUUGGGAUUGUAUUGAUUUUGUAUUUUCCCAAAAUAGUACUUUGAAUUGAUAGUCCUUUAUGCAAUGUCUUAGCAAUAGUCUCUAUAAUGCCCAUCCAGGAGAAGUGGGUAGUAAUUCUUCAUCAUGAAAAUGAUAUAUUACAUAUUUAGUAUCUUCCCUUUGCAGUAUUGCACUUUUGUUUAACUAGAAUACACCUAUGAGAUAGCCAAAGUUUCAAACACAGUUAUCUUAGUUUACCGGUGGAGUAUUUCAACACCAACCACAUUUCCCUUCCUCCCUCUAAUUCUACCCACAUGAUCUUUAUUCCUUCCUUUCGCCAAUUAAAAAAAAAAAAAAGGAAAAAAAAUCUGUAGAUCUUGUCACUAAAAUCUAAUUUAUAUCAAAUUUAUGAGAGAAAGUAUUUUCCUAAUUAUGGUCAAAUAAAUUUGGUUAACAUCCUAGUGAUUCUCUUUCUAUAUAAUAAGGCAAUUACAGUUUUCAAAGCAUUAAGUCUAACAUAACUUUAAACAUUCUCUUAGGUUUCAAGACACUUCUAUUUAAUAUUCAUUGGGGAAAAGUUGUCCAGCUAUCAGCUAAGAAAACACAUGCAAAUAUGGUUGUGUAAAGUUAAGGGUUAUAAGGAAAAAAAAAUCAGUAGAAUUACAUAAUACUAAAGUUGCAGUUGAAAGAAUAUCCAAGUAUGUGUUGGUAGUUACUAAAAGAAUUAUAGCUGUUAUUGCCUUGUAUUUAUAGCCCUUGUUUCAGGUUUUAUGAUUCAAGUCUUAGUCCAAUCUUUCUUUUGGACAUUUGCAAUAUUUACCAGUUGUGUUUUGUGUAGUCUGAAUUUGCUUUCUGUAGUUGAGCAAACGUCUUAAAAAGUCAUUUGUAAUUUAUUAAAUUACUUUCUAUGAUGUUCUAUAGAGCAAAUGGAAGUUUAAUUAUUUUUUAUUAAACAUAUUCUUUGACUACC